AACUUGCUUUUGGGAGCCAGCGGUAUGGCGUCGGGCUGCAAGAUUGGCCCGUCCAUCCUCAACAGCGACCUGGCCAAUUUAGGGGCCGAGUGCCUCCGGAUGCUAGACUCUGGGGCCGAUUAUCUGCACCUGGACGUAAUGGACGGGCAUUUUGUUCCCAACAUCACCUUUGGUCACCCUGUGGUAGAAAGCCUUCGAAAGCAGCUAGGCCAGGACCCUUUCUUUGACAUGCACAUGAUGGUGUCCAAGCCAGAACAGUGGGUAAAGCCAAUGGCUGUAGCAGGAGCCAAUCAGUACACCUUUCAUCUCGAGGCUACUGAGAACCCAGGGGCUUUGAUUAAAGACAUUCGGGAGAAUGGGAUGAAGGUUGGCCUUGCCAUCAAACCAGGAACCUCAGUUGAGUAUUUGGCACCAUGGGCUAAUCAGAUAGAUAUGGCCUUGGUUAUGACAGUGGAACCGGGGUUUGGAGGGCAGAAAUUCAUGGAAGAUAUGAUGCCAAAGGUUCACUGGUUGAGGACCCAGUUCCCAUCUUUGGAUAUAGAGGUCGAUGGUGGAGUAGGUCCUGACACUGUCCAUAAAUGUGCAGAGAUUGGAGUGCAGUGGCGUGAUCUCUGCUCACUGCAAUCUCUGCCUGCCGGGUUCAAGCGAUUCUCCUGCCUCAGCCUCCUGAGUAGCUGGGAUUACAGGCAGGAGCUAACAUGAUUGUGUCUGGCAGUGCUAUUAUGAGGAGUGAAGACCCCAGAUCUGUGAUCAAUCUAUUAAGAAAUGUUUGCUCAGAAGCUGCUCAGAAACGUUCUCUUGAUCGGUGAAACCAUAAGGAGCCCAGUGUUCCUGUUCAUGAAAUCUCCCUUUUACUGGAAAACAGGAAUAUUGACUACCAAAUCACAAUGCAAUUGAAGCCGUACUGCUUUUUUGAGCAGUUAUUCAUUCCAGUGAUUAAAACUGAUUGUGCAGAAUAUUCUAAGAGGUCAGAAAUUGGUGUGUAUAACUACAUUUUUAGUGAUGCAAUUUAUUGAUUAGUGAGUAAGAUACUGUUUUUAUUGAGAGAUUUGAUUUUUAUAAAGUAAAAAUACGGCUGCAUUAGGGUUACAAACAGAAAAGUGUCUUAAUGUCUAAGGAGGGCAUAUUAGCUACACUACAAAAACAAAUUUUGUCUGUACUUCUGAAAAGAAUUUUGUUGUUUCUCAGCUGUUUUCCAAAAGCAAAGGAAGUCUUUAUGGUUUUUUUCUAUUUCAUGUUAUUGUGAUUUGUUUAUAAGUUUGGGUGGGGUGCAUACCAUAUUCUUGGUUCUUAAAAUCUAUCACUUUUCACCUUACACUUGAUGUGUGAAAACUAUAAAAACAAUGUGUGAAACCCAGGGGUUCUAAAAUACAAGCAUAGAUUUUAUCAGGGUGUUUUGUCAAAGCAGGUUAUUCAGUGAUUCCUCCCCACCAUUCUUAAGAACGUUAAAUAAUGCUGUUGUGUUAGCUCUGAGUAGAAAGGAAAAAGUAAAACCUCUGUUUGGAGGUAAUAUUGGGUUGAAUUCUGACUGCCCCUUUCUAGCUGGACCUUUAACAAAUCACCCAAUCUUUUUUGUGUUUCUCUAAAGUCAUUUAUACAUUAAAUGUAAUUAUAGCAACUGUGGGGUUCUGUUGAGAAUUAAGAGCUAACACUAUAUAUGUAAAGUUUCCAGUACUAGUCCCAGAAUUUAGAAUAUGCUCAACACAAAGUAAACAGCAUUAUAUAAGUUUAUAUUUUUGUGAGUUAUAAAGUACUUUGAUAUAUUCUCAUUAAAUCUGUAAAUCACCUCUAUAAGUAAGUGGUAAUAAUAAAGCAGAUAUUUUUGUCCCCAUUUAAAAAAUGAAGAAAUUAAUGCUUAAUAGGGUGGUACCCUGGAAAGGAUCUGGGAAGUGGUAGAAUUUCUGGUCUGUACUUUUACAAAUGGAGCCCUUGGGAGGUGGGUUAGGUAAAAGAAGCUUUUUACUUAACGUUGUCUUAUUUCCAGUCUAAUUUUACGCUGUAGCAGAACCAGAUGGCUGAGAAAAUUCUGGAACUAUGGAUCUUGACCCCAAGGAUAUAUUAUUUUAUUCCAAGAAAGAUCAGGUAGGCGAAAAGAUGACAGGAUACAGAGUCAAUCCAUAAACUAAAUAUUUAUAACUGUUCUGAAUUAUACAGAGUCUAAAAAUAUGUGUCAGCUACUUCAUUCCUGUAAAUACUCUUGCUGUGUUAUAAAUAUGGCAAGAAAUAAACAUGACCAAUAUCAAUAGACUUCUUGAGGCUACUAUAAGUUUUGAGAAAUAAGGUUCAAAAAAUAAGAAUGCUAACACUUAAGCACAGACUAGAGCUUGCUUGGGUUUCUUCCUGCAUUACAAGGUAAAAAUUUGUUAAUGUUUGUUUUUAUUCAGCUUGGGAAAGCUUUGUGCCAUGAAUACGUCGCAUUUAAUAACAAGCAACACACGGCAUAUAGAAAUAACUUUAAUUAAAAAACUUACAUAGAAGAUUAUAAUAUCAGACGUGACAAAGAUUUGAGUUUAUUUGCCUGGACAACUUGGGUUUGUCUGGCUUUUGUUUUCUUUUUCUUUAAAAAUAAAUGUACAGUAAAACUACAAGCAAAAGUUUGUCAGUAUUGAAUUGAAUUUUUUACCCCUUAAAAGGACUAGUAUAAUUUCCAAUCUCUAACAAAAACUUAGUGUCAAAUCUCACAGAUAAGGCCAAAUGGCCAAUAUUUUCAGUUAUGUGGGUAGUACAACUUGAGUAACCUUUUUUACAUGACAAAAAGUGAGUUAUAUAAAUUGUCCUCAACUUUCACAUAGGAAAAAAAUGGUUUAAUAGCUUCAAAAGGAAUUUUCUUUCAUGUAUACUCUUCAGUAUCCAAUAUUGAAGCUUUGUUCUUUGAAAAAUUUUAAUUUCCAAUCUAGGAUGCAAGCAAGAAUAUAUGUUUAUUUGAAUAGAGUAAGCUAUGGCAAAGAAUGACCAAAUUAGCUAGAAAUAGAAAUCAGCCAGAAUUAACUAAUUUCUUGCUAAUCUAGAAAUACAAUCAUCUUUUUUUUUUUUUUCAAAUUUUAUACUGAUAGGGCUUUACUGUUUGUGGCUCAUUUUAAAACUGGUGUCUUCUCUUCAUGAGACACAUUAAUUGGUAAAACUCAAAUUGAGUUUUCAAAGAUGUGAUAGUAUUAAAGUGCACCAAUAUUUGACUCAAAUUUGCUUGCUUUAUUUUGUUAGGAGUAAACAGAAAGUAGCCUGUGUUUAGUCCCAAAGAUAGCAGUGAUUUUGAAUAAAGGAGUUUUGUGUUGCCUGGA